UGGCCAGGUUGGUCUCGAACUCCUGAUCUCAAGUCAUCUACCCUCCUUGGCCUCCCAACUCUGAGUUUGUUUUUAGAACAAGCUGAGGUGCAGAGAGUCAGCCUCUGACCUGAGGUCUUCUUCUCUUCCCCAGGCUCCUUGAACUAUGAAGUUUGCAUGUGCGUGUCUGUGGAACUCCAGCCUGUACACCCUCCAAACAGCAGCUCUUUGGCCAUUCUUUGGCCUAGGGUUGUAAAUACUGUUGGUUGGGUCAUCUGUCCUUAGGAGAACUGACUCAGGGGAGAGGCCUGAGCAGACCCUGGAAGAGGAAGAUGAAGUCCUCAGUACAUUCUGAAGAAGAUGAUUUUGUUCCAGAGCUACAUAGAAAUGUACACCCUCGAGAGCGGCCUGAUUGGGAAGAAACUCUUAGCGCAAUGGCAAGAGGCGCAGAUGUUCCAGAGAUUCCUGGAGAUCUUACUCUUAAGACGUGUGGCAGUACAGCCAGUAUGAAGGUUAAGCAUGUGAAAAAGUCCACCACUCCAGGACUGAUGGGCUGUGACAACAUUCACAGGUUACCCUUCACUAAAGGUCACUUUCCGAAGAUGGCUGAAUGUGCGCAUUUCCAUUAUGAGAAUGUUGAGUUCGGCAGCAUACAGCUUUCACUUUCAGAAGAACAGAAUGAAGUAAUGAAAAAUGGCUGUGAAUCUAAAGAGCUGGUCUACCUCGUGCAGAUUGCUUGUCAGGGAAAAAGUUGGAUUGUUAAAAGAAGUUAUGAAGAUUUUCGGGUACUUGAUAAACAUCUUCAUCUGUGUAUUUAUGACCGAAGAUUUUCCCAGCUCUCAGAACUUCCCCGUUCUGACACCCUGAAGGACAGUCCAGAGUCGGUCACUCAGAUGCUUAUGGCUUACCUGUCACGCCUUUCAGCUAUCGCUGGCAACAAGAUCAACUGUGGGCCCGCCCUUACCUGGAUGGAGAUUGAUAAUAAGGGAAAUCACCUUUUGGUUCAUGAGGAGUCAUCCAUCAACACUCCUGCUGUCGGUGCUGCCCAUGUUAUCAAGAGGUACACUGCUCGGGCCCCUGACGAACUGACCUUAGAGGUGGGAGACAUUGUUUCUGUUAUUGACAUGCCCCCGAAAGUGUUAAGCACAUGGUGGAGAGGCAAGCACGGAUUCCAGGUGGGACUCUUCCCUGGACACUGUGUUGAGUUAAUUAACCAAAAAGUUCCCCAGUCAGUGACCAACUCAGUGCCAAAACCAGUGUCUAAAAAGCACGGCAAGCUCAUUACGUUCUUACGAACAUUCAUGAAGUCUCGUCCAACAAAACAGAAGCUGAAGCAGCGGGGAAUCUUGAAAGAGAGGGUGUUUGGUUGUGACCUGGGGGAACACCUUCUAAAUUCUGGUUUUGAAGUGCCGCAGGUUCUUCAAAGCUGCACAGCAUUCAUUGAGAGAUAUGGCAUCGUGGAUGGAAUCUAUCGCCUUUCUGGUGUUGCCUCCAAUAUCCAGAGACUACGCCAUGAAUUUGACUCUGAGCACGUCCCCGACCUGACGAAAGAACCGUAUGUUCAGGACAUCCAUUCUGUGGGUUCCCUAUGUAAGCUGUACUUCCGGGAACUCCCAAACCCUCUGCUUACCUACCAGCUGUAUGAGAAAUUUUCUGAUGCAGUUUCAGCAGCAACAGAUGAAGAAAGGCUGAUAAAAAUCCACGAUGUCAUCCAGCAGCUCCCCCCACCACACUACAGAACACUGGAGUUCCUGAUGAGACACUUGUCUCUUCUAGCUGACUAUUGUUCCAUCACAAAUAUGCAUGCAAAAAAUCUAGCAAUUGUUUGGGCUCCAAACCUGUUAAGAUCAAAACAGAUAGAAUCUGCCUGCUUCAGUGGAACAGCAGCUUUCAUGGAAGUGAGGAUUCAGUCUGUGGUUGUUGAGUUCAUCCUGAAUCACGUUGAUGUGCUGUUCAGCGGCAGAAUCAGCAUGGCCAUGCAAGAGGGGGCAGCUUCUCUAUCAAGGCCCAAGUCCCUCCUGGUAUCCUCUCCAUCCACCAAACUGCUGACAUUGGAAGAGGCCCAGGCACGAACACAAGCUCAGGUCAAUUCUCCAAUUGUGACGGAAAAUAAAUAUAUCGAAGUAGGAGAAGGACCUGCUGCACUUCAGGGGAAAUUUCAUACCAUAAUUGAGUUCCCACUUGAAAGAAAGAGGCCUCAAAAUAAGAUGAAAAAGUCUCCUGUGGGUAGCUGGCGUUCCUUUUUCAACUUGGGGAAAUCAUCAUCUGUUUCUAAACGAAAGCUGCAGCGGAAUGAGAGUGAGCCUUCAGAGAUGAAAGCCAUGGCUCUGAAAGGUGGCAGGGCAGAAGGAACCCUCCGUUCAGCUAAAAGUGAGGAGUCUCUUACAUCUCUCCAUGCAGUUGAUGGUGAUUCUAAGCUCUUCCGACCCAGAAGACCCAGAUCUUCCAGUGAUGCACUGUCUGCCUCUUUUAAUGGAGAAAUGCUGGGGAACCGCUGUAACUCCUAUGAUAAUCUGCCUCAUGACAAUGAGAGUGAGGAGGAAGGAGGGCUGCUUCAUAUCCCAGCCCUUAUGUCUCCUCAUUCAGCUGAGGAUGUUGACUUGAGCCCACCAGACAUUGGAGUAGCCAGCCUGGAUUUUGAUCCAAUGUCAUUUCAAUGUAGUCCUCCUAAGGCCGAAUCAGAAUGUCUGGAGAGUGGUGCUUCCUUUUUAGAUUCACCAGGAUACUCCAAGGAUAAACCAAGUGCCAAUAAAAAGGAUGCAGAAACAGGUAGUAGCCAAUGUCAGACUCCAGGAAGCACAGCAAGCUCUGAACCUGUCUCUCCUCUUCAGGAGAAACUGAGUCCAUUCUUUACCCUGGACUUGAGCCCAACUGAAGAUAAAUCAUCUAAGCCAUCCUCCUUUACUGAAAAGGUCGUCUAUGCUUUCUCUCCGAAGAUAGGACGGAAAUUAAGCAAAUCACCUUCUAUGAGCAUAUCUGAGCCAAUUUCAGUGACCCUACCACCACGGGUGUCAGAAGUCAUUGGUACAGUCUCAAAUACCACAGCUCAGAAUGCAUCAUCUUCAACCUGGGACAAAUGCGUUGAAGAAAGGGAUGCCACAAAUAGAUCCCCCACCCAGAUAGUAAAGAUGAAAACAAAUGAGACAGUUGCCCAAGAAGCAUAUGAAUCUGAAGUCCAGCCCCUGGACCAGGUGGCUGCUGAAGAAGUAGAAUUGCCAGGGAAAGAGGAUCAGUCUGUCUCAAGCAGUCAGAGUAAGGCUGUAGCUUCUGGACAGACUCAGACAGGAGCAGUUACCCAUGACCCCCCUCAGGAUUCCGUUCCUGUCAGUUCAGUCUCUCUUAUCCCACCACCACCGCCUCCGAAAAAUGUUGCCCGAAUGUUGGCGCUAGCAUUAGCUGAGUCCGCACAGCAAGCCUCAACUCAGUCAUUGAAGAGACCAGGGACCUCUCAGGCUGGGUAUACAAAUUAUGGAGACAUAGCGGUGGCUACAACUGAAGAUAAUCUGUCCAGUUCUUACUCUGCAGUUGCUCUAGAUAAGGCCUAUUUCCAAACCGAUCGACCAGCAGAGCAGUUCCACCUCCAGAAUAAUGCACCAGGAAACUGUGACCAUCCUCUACCAGAGACAACAGCUACUGGGGAUCCUACCCAUUCCAACACAACUGAAUCUGGGGAGCAACAUCACCAAGUAGACUUAACAGGGAAUCAGCCACAUCAAGCAUAUUUAUCUGGGGACCCAGAAAAGGCCAGAAUUACUUCAGUUCCCUUAGACUCAGAGAAGUCUGAUGAUCAUGUAAGUUUCCCUGAAGACCAGUCUGGGAAGAACAGUAUGCCAACUGUCUCCUUCUUGGAUCAGGACCAGUCUCCACCCCGUUUCUACAGUGGAGAUCAGCCUCCUUCUUAUCUUGGUGCAAGUGUGGAUAAACUCCAUCACCCUUUAGAAUUUGCAGACAAAUCUCCCACACCUCCUAAUUUACCUAGCGAUAAAAUCUACCCUCCUUCUGGGUCCCCCGAAGAGAAUACCAGCACAGCCACCAUGACUUACAUGACAACUACUCCAGCAACAGCCCAAAUGAGCACCAAGGAAGCCAGCUGGGAUGUGGCUGAACAACCCACCACUGCUGAUUUUGCUGCUGCCACACUUCAGCGCACGCACAGAACUAAUCGUCCCCUUCCCCCUCCGCCUUCCCAGAGAUCUGCAGAGCAGCCACCAGUUGUGGGGCAGGUACAAGCAGCAACCAAUAUAGGAUUAAAUAAUUCCCACAAGGUUCAAGGAGUAGUUCCAGUUCCAGAGAGGCCACCUGAACCUCGAGCCAUGGAUGACCCUGCGUCUGCCUUCAUCAGUGACAGUGGUGCUGCUGCUGCUCAGUGUCCCAUGGCUACAGCUGUCCAGCCAGGCCUGCCUGAGAAAGUGCGGGACGGUGCCCGGGUCCCGCUGCUGCACCUGCGCGCCGAGUCUGUCCCUGCGCAUCCCUGUGGCUUUCCUGCACCACUGCCCCCCACCAGGAUGAUGGAGAGUAAGAUGAUUGCUGCCAUACACUCCAGCAGUGCAGAUGCCACCAGCAGUUCAAAUUAUCAUUCCUUUGUCACUGCUUCAUCCACCUCUGUGGACGAUGCAUUGCCUUUACCACUUCCUGUCCCACAACCUAAGCAUGCUUCUCAGAAAACAGUUUACUCCUCCUUUGCUAGGCCCGAUGUCACCACUGAACCCUUUGGUCCAGAUAACUGUUUGCAUUUCAAUAUGACUCCAAACUGCCAGUACCGUCCCCAGAGUGUACCUCCCCAUCACAAUAAAUUGGAGCAGCACCAAGUGUAUGGUGCCAGGUCAGAGCCACCAGCCUCCAUGGGUCUUCGUUAUAACACAUAUGUGGCCCCAGGAAGAAACGCAUCUGGACACCACUCCAAGCCAUGCAGCCGGGUCGAGUAUGUGUCUUCUUUGAGCUCCUCUGUCAGGAAUACCUGUUACCCCGAAGACAUUCCACCGUACCCUACCAUCCGGAGAGUGCAGUCUCUCCAUGCUCCGCCGUCUUCCAUGAUUCGCUCUGUUCCCAUUUCACGGACAGAAGUUCCCCCAGAUGAUGAGCCAGCCUACUGCCCAAGACCUCUGUACCAAUAUAAGCCAUAUCAGUCCUCCCAGGCCCGCUCAGAUUAUCAUGUCACUCAGCUUCAGCCUUACUUUGAGAAUGGCCGGGUCCACUACAGGUAUAGCCCAUAUUCCAGUUCUUCUAGUUCCUAUUACAGUCCAGAUGGGGCCCUGUGUGAUGUGGAUGCCUAUGGCACAGUCCAGUUGAGACCCCUUCACCGCCUUCCCAAUCGAGACUUUGCUUUCUACAAUCCUAGGCUGCAAGGAAAGAGCUUGUACAGUUAUGCUGGUUUGGCUCCACGUCCCCGGGCCAACGUGACUGGCUAUUUCUCUCCCAACGACCAUAAUGUAGUCAGCAUGCCUCCGGCUGCUGAUGUGAAGCACACCUACACCUCAUGGGAUCUUGAGGACAUGGAAAAAUACCGCAUGCAGUCCAUCCGGAGAGAGAGCCGUGCUCGGCAGAAGGUGAAAGGGCCUGUCAUGUCCCAAUAUGAUAACAUGACCCCGGCGGUGCAGGACGACUUGGGUGGGAUCUAUGUCAUCCAUCUGCGUAGUAAAUCAGAUCCUGGGAAAACUGGACUUCUCUCAGUGGCAGAAGGAAAGGAGAGCCGCCAUGCAGCCAAGGCCAUCAGUCCCGAGGGAGAGGACCGCUUCUAUAGGAGGCAUCCCGAGGCAGAGAUGGACAGAGCCCACCAUCACGGAGGCCAUGGUAGCACGCAGCCGGAGAAGCCAUCCCUGCCUCAGAAGCAGAGCAGCCUGAGGAGCAGGAAGCUUCCUGACAUGGGCUGCAGUCUUCCUGAGCACAGGGCACACCAAGAAGCAAGCCAUAGGCAGUUCUGUGAGUCAAAGAAUGGGCCCCCUUAUCCCCAGGGAGCUGGCCAGUUAGAUUAUGGGUCCAAAGGGAUUCCAGACACUUCUGAGCCAGUCAGCUACCACAACUCUGGAGUAAAAUAUGCUGCAUCCGGGCAAGAAUCUUUAAGACUGAACCACAAAGAGGUAAGGCUCUCCAAAGAGAUGGAGCGACCCUGGGUUAGGCAGCCUUCUGCCCCAGAGAAACACUCCAGAGACUGCUACAAGGAGGAAGAACACCUCACUCAGUCAAUCGUCCCACCCCCUAAACCAGAGAGGAGUCAUAGCCUCAAACUCCAUCAUACCCAGAACGUGGAGAGGGACCCCAGUGUGCUGUACCAGUACCAACCACACGGCAAGCGCCAGAGCAGUGUGACUGUUGUGUCCCAGUAUGAUAACCUGGAAGAUUACCACUCCCUGCCUCAGCACCAGCGAGGAGUCUUUGGAGGGGGCGGCAUGGGGACGUAUGUGCCCCCUGGCUUUCCCCAUCCACAGAGCAGGACCUAUGCUACAGCGUUGGGUCAAGGGGCCUUCCUGCCCGCAGAGUUGUCCUUGCAGCAUCCUGAAACACAGAUCCAUGCAGAAUGAGCCCUGCGAGCAAUAGAGUUGAAGCAGCCUCUGCUGGACAGUGGACUGUUCUAUUUUUUUCAAUAACCAAAAAGAUUAAACAAAAAAUACUAUAAAACCCCUGACCACAUUUAAAAAAUGAUAAUAAAAGUAAACAAAUCAGCAUCUUUUUCCCCUUCCCUGCUUCAUUACCCCCUCUUCCAUCUAUAGACUUUGUCAUUUUUGUCUUUAGAAAAGAUCUGAAGGAUGGUAAAGCCCCGUGCUGAAACCCAGUAGAGAAACCUGUCUCAGGACACACUUGCCAUCUAGGGCUAGCUUGAAAGAGCCUGAGGACUGCCUUUAACUGAAUUUGAAUUCAGCAUUGUCCUUUCUUCUUAGUAUUUGCUGCAUAAUUGAGAGCAGUUCACAUCGAUUUCCUGGUAGGCGUCUGCAUUCCCUGUUGUGUUCCUGCUUCUCCUUCAGUAGCUGCACAACUUGCGCAGAUCGACACACUGUUGUCACUUCAUUCUCCCCGUCUGAGAAGGAUCUUGUGUUCAGUUAGAGUCGUGGAAAAAUCCCUGAUCCUUCAAGGUCAGUCAGACAGUUGGCAACAUUAUAAUUAAAAAUAAGAAAUUAAGACUUUAAAUUAAACAUUUGGUAGAGUCAUCAUAAAACACCAGACCACUUAGACUCAGGCUGAACCAUACUCUUUCUAUUCUUAUUUUUCAUCCUUGUUCCUCACGGUUCAGUGAACAGGCUCAUAUCAUGACAGAAUGGACUUUUAAAAGUUAGUACUUAAGGAAACUUCUUUAGGUGGAAGAAAGUAAAGUUCUUAUUGUCAGUGAACUUUAUUAGCACCAGAAAUCUCUAUUGAUGCUUUUAAUGCAUUGCCUGCCUUCAGGUUUUCUUCUUACCCCACCCCUCAAUAAGAUUUGGUGAAUUGUAAUUCUAGUAAAACAUGUCAUACCAUUGGUUUUCCUAAAUUAUCAACUUUCUUUCAUUAAAAAAAAAAAAAAAAAAAAAAGCCCAGCAUGGUUUGACUGGAUAGACACGCAUAAUUUAUUAUGAAUAUAAAUUUCCAUGUUUGUUUCUGUUCCUAAACCAGAGUACGAGGUCCCUGGGAAUUUAAGUAGCUACGCAUUAUCUAUUAUUAGACUGCAAGUUCCUGCAAUAACUGCUUAGUUCACAGCCCCGUUUCACCAGUGGAGUUCUGGGCAGUUAUUGCUGUCCUAAGGCAUUACUGUCGUUUGCUUACUCUAUACUUGUGUGGUCACAGUCUUCUUGUAAUUACCAUCUACACCAGCAUUUCAGGUAUAGCUCUUUAUAACUCUGGAGACAUGUAAAACAUGUUUAACACCCACGAGUUUUGAAAGUUGCAUUCCUUAUUAGAGUAGGAACUCUCUAGCCCAACUCCAUUCUAUGUUCUCAGCUCCCUCCACCCCCCAAAAUACAUCAGACUAGCAAGGCAGUCCUAUGUUUACAAAACGAGUUUAGAUUGUCAUUUCAUUCCAUAACUCUUAAUAAUACUCAAGUUUUAUACAUUCACGUAUUUUAAAUGCUCGGUCUGUAGAAGACACUAGGAGAAUUGCAUUCCAAUUACUGGAUGGUUGCUGCUCUGGCUUUUUAGAACUUGAAAUUAAUUUUUAUUUAGAGCAAAGGAGGAAAUCUUUUAAGAGGCUAAAAUCAUGCUGCUAUUAUUGCUGUGAAAUUGUAUAAAGAUUAGGAUUCAUGCCAGUUUUUAUUUUAAAAAAUAAUGUGCAUUUUAAGGGUUUAUAUUUAGAAAAAAAUAAAAUGUUUCAAGAACAACACAUUGAUAUGUGGAAAUAUUCUAUAAGGUUUUCUUUUGUUCCCUUAGAAUUCAUUGGAGGGAUGCAGUAAAAACUGUAGUAGAAACCUUGAAACACCCAUAUGUGAAAAGGUCUGUGGAAAUUGAGGCCUCUACAUUAAAAGUGCAGAACCAACUGUUUUACAGUCAAAGUGCUAGGAAACCUGAUAGGAUACUUCCCUUUGGCACAAAAACACCCUGGGUGCUACAUACAGGAGUAUGACCUUUGGUGAAUAUGUGGCACUAAUUUUUUUUACCUUAAUCAUAUUCUUGUCAAGUAGGCAACCCAUUGCCCCUUGGAGACCACACCAGCCCUGUAAGUUCUCACCAGCAGCAUGGAGAUUAGGAAGAGGGGCUGCUGUGACCAGGAGAUACACACGGCUUUAAGUAACUGAGAGCCUAAAGAAAGUAACCCAGGGAGUCCGGUCCAGUUUUAAUAUUUGUGGAUUUGUUGUCACACACAUUGUUUAGUCCUGAAACUAAAACCUAUUUUAUAAAUAGUAGGGUUAAUUCCUCGAAACAAUUUCUUUAUUAAUAAAUGUCCUGUGGGUUUAGAAAUAUCAGGUAAAUAUUUGAAUACAGAAUGAUGAUUGCAAUUACUGUUACAAGCGUGAAACACAAACUUCAGAUCAAAUCUAGAGUUGCUUCAUUUAAUGCAUGCUAGCAACAGCCUUAACUUUGGAUUCAGUUAUUUGAAACACUUUUCCGGCAUCUUUCCCUUUCUAAUGUUGUGGGGUGGAAACCGGAUGGCAAAUCACUGUGAGCCGGAUACCUCAGCACAGUCCACCUUGUGUGUGACUUCACAAAUGGGGGACUUCACAAAUGGGGUAACUGAAUGUUAUUACUUUCAAAUUUUGACAUGGAGCAUUAUGAUCAAGGAAAUGGAGCUGCCUUAUACAUUAAACCCGUGAUUUAAUCCUAUUGACAUUUUCAUAGCCAUGCCUCCAGAUUUUAUCUUUUUGGCAAAAUUCUGAUUCCACAGUUUGGUCUGAUUGAAAUAAAUAUUCCCUGGACGUCUGGCUAAAAAUUUUGCUAACAAUCCCAGAGGUGCCAUUUUCUUAUUAAUAAAUUUCAUUGGAGCCUUAUUUCUUACUAUAUUCAAUUUCGUUUCAAACCUGCAAGUCCCUGGGAUGGUCCCACGACUAGGGCCUGCACAUUUCUUACAAUGGCAAAGCAUUUUUUAAAAUUUAGGGUCAGGUUGAAAAAUUCUAGGACUAAUUCUGUAGAGAGGAGGGACUGUUAACUAACGUGAGUGGGGACGGAGGAGUAGGUUACCACAUUUGGAGCAGUAAUAGAUGCAAACGAUGUAAAUUUGAAAUUUGCCCCUUUAGUUAAAGAAGGAGCCUGCAAAGUCCAUUUCUCUGUUUUCAGCCCUGUCAGUCACCCAUUUAGGAUGUUGGCAAAGUACUGCUUGAGCAGAAUGUGUAAGAAAGUAAUAAUGAAAGCAAAAGUAUGUCAGACAGUUACUUCUUCCACAUGGUUAGAGGCAUGUGAUUUUCAGCACUGUGUGUUACAGAAAUGUCAGGAAUGGUGUAUUAUAACGUGUGCAAGAUAAUGUCAGUGUGCACAGAGGGUCUUUUUUCCUUAUCUGAUUAGUACUGUUAAUGUUCAAAGAAUAAAAAUGGUUUUACAGUUUAGAUUCUGAGAUAGCAAAACCUGAUUUUUCAACCAUGACCUGCAUGAGAGAAGCAUCCUAGGAAGUCUUAGAUCAUACUUUUGAGUUUUUAAUUUUAAUUUAUAUAGUGUUUUUUUAUGUCUUAAUAUUUUUGUGAACUGGUGUAAAUUGUUAAUGCAUAUAAGCUUGUGUAUUUUUGUAAAUAGUUUUGUGAUUUAUUUCUUGCCCCAUAUGUAAAUAUUUAGAGUCUCAUUUCUUGCAAACUUAUUUGAAGCUGAGUUGUGGGUUUGGGUUUUGUUUGUUUCUUUGGUUGCAGGGUGGGGUGGGGGGUGGCAGGGGAGGGAGGAAGGGAUUUUUGUACCUGGAGAUGGAGAUAUCUUGUGGUUUAAAGCAAAUGUCCCACUGAAAGUGAUUCAAAUAUCAACAGAAUUAUUUCAGGUUAAAACAGA